AGACGGAAGUGCGGGCGGAGGAUCCCCAGCCGGGUCCCAAGCCUGUGCCUGAGCCUGAGCCUGAGCCUGAGCCCGAGCCGGGAGCCGGUCGCGGGGGCUCCGGGCUGUGGGACCGCUGGGCCCCCAGCGAUGGCGACCCUGUGGGGAGGCCUUCUUCGGCUUGGCUCCUUGCUCAGCCUGUCGUGCCUGGCGCUUUCCGUGCUGCUGCUGGCGCAGCUGUCAGACGCCGCCAAGAAUUUCGAGGAUGUCAGAUGUAAAUGUAUCUGCCCUCCCUAUAAAGAAAAUUCUGGGCAUAUUUAUAAUAAGAACAUAUCUCAGAAAGAUUGUGAUUGCCUUCAUGUUGUGGAGCCCAUGCCUGUGCGGGGGCCUGAUGUAGAAGCAUACUGUCUACGCUGUGAAUGCAAAUAUGAAGAAAGAAGCUCUGUCACAAUCAAGGUUACCAUUAUAAUUUAUCUCUCCAUUUUGGGCCUUCUACUUCUGUACAUGGUAUAUCUUACUCUGGUUGAGCCCAUACUGAAGAGGCGCCUCUUUGGACAUGCACAGUUGAUACAGAGUGAUGAUGAUAUUGGGGAUCACCAGCCUUUUGCAAAUGCACACGAUGUGCUAGCCCGCUCCCGCAGUCGAGCCAACGUGCUGAACAAGGUAGAAUAUGCACAGCAGCGCUGGAAGCUUCAAGUCCAAGAGCAGCGAAAGUCUGUCUUUGACCGGCAUGUUGUCCUCAGCUAAUUGGGAAUUGAAUUCAAGGUGACUAGAAAGAAACAGGCAGACAACUGGAAAGAACUGACUGGGUUUUGCUGGGUUUCAUUUUAAUACCUUGUUGAUUUCACCAACUGUUGCUGGAAGAUUCAAAACUGGAAGCAAAAACUUGCUUGAUUUUUUUUUCUUGUUAACGUAAUAAUAGAGACAUUUUUAAAAGCACACAGCUCAAAGUCAGCCAAUAAGUCUUUUCCUAUUUGUGACUUUUACUAAUAAAAAUAAAUCUGCCUGUAAAUUAUCUUGAAGUCCUUUACCUGGAACAAGCACUCUCUUUUUCACCACAUAGUUUUAACUUGACUUUCAAGAUAAUUUUCAGGGUUUUUGUUGUUGUUGUUUUUUGUUUGUUUGUUUUGGUGGGAGAGGGGAGGGAUGCCUGGGAAGUGGUUAACAACUUUUUUCAAGUCACUUUACUAAACAAACUUUUGUAAAUAGACCUUACCUUCUAUUUUCGAGUUUCAUUUAUAUUUUGCAGUGUAGCCAGCCUCAUCAAAGAGCUGACUUACUCAUUUGACUUUUGCACUGACUGUAUUAUCUGGGUAUCUGCUGUGUCUGCACUUCAUGGUAAACGGGAUCUAAAAUGCCUGGUGGCUUUUCACAAAAAGCAGAUUUUCUUCAUGUACUGUGAUGUCUGAUGCAAUGCAUCCUAGAACAAACUGGCCAUUUGCUAGUUUACUCUAAAGACUAAACAUAGUCUUGGUGUGUGUGGUCUUACUCAUCUUCUAGUACCUUUAAGGACAAAUCCUAAGGACUUGGACACUUGCAAUAAAGAAAUUUUAUUUUAAACCCAAGCCUCCCUGGAUUGAUAAUAUAUACACAUUUGUCAGCAUUUCCGGUCGUGGUGAGAGGCAGCUGUUUGAGCUCCAAUGUGUGCAGCUUUGAACUAGGGCUGGGGUUGUGGGUGCCUCUUCUGAAAGGUCUAACCAUUAUUGGAUAACUGGCUUUUUUCUUCCUAUGUCCUCUUUGGAAUGUAACAAUAAAAAUAAUUUUUGAAACAUCCAUCAGUGUAUCUAUCUAUGUCUCCUAGUUUUUUCCUCCUCCCUCUUUUGCUGUAUAAUGAGAUUGAAGAUAUAAAGACAUUUUGUACCCUG